AGAACGGCCCGGGCGGAACCAACGGGCAGCCGCGGGGGCGUUGUGGGCCGCGGCGCGUUUCCCCGGCUCCGUGGCUCUGGGGCACUGAGGAGCGGCGCCCGCGGGGCAGCGAGGAGCCCGAUGCAGGGUUCUGCGCGUCAUUUCCGGUCCCGCGGGCGCCCCGUGAAGCCCACCUGGAUCCGCCAGCGCUGUGCCACUCCCCAGUGCCGAGCUCCGAGCUGUCUCCGCGGCCUCGCGCCCGGCCCCUCCACCGCGCGCCUCUCAGGCCCCGCCCGCCAGCGUCCCUUUGUUGUGAAGGCGCCGGGGCCUAGCGCUAUGCCUGCGGCGGAGACUGCAUCAGGCUCUCGUCCUCGGGCUCCACCCGGGGAGCUGUGCCCAGACAGCAGAAGGGAAGGAUGUCACUUCUGAGAUGAGGUUCAGAAAGGUCUGGGCUCCUGUCCUGGCUGCUCUCUCCCACUCCCUGAUGAGCUUGCUGGAUGAAAGCUCCUGUCAGGCUGUGGGGCGUCCUGUGGAGAAGCUGGCAAGAAACUGGUGGGGGCCCUUUCCACCUAUAGCCAGCAAGGAACUGAACCCAGCCAGCGUCCACCUGAGUGAGCUCAGAGGUGGGCCUCAGCCCCAGUUGAGCCUUCGGAUGAGGUCACAGCCCUGGUCCAUGGUGUGACUGCAGCUUCAGGAGGGACCUUAAGCCAGAGGUGCCUGGCUAAGCUUCCCGCAGAUUGCUGCCCCACAGGAGCCAACAUCAAAAGCAUUUGUUGUUUUGAGGUGCGUCUGCUUCUGCGCUUUGCCUGGGAGAGGCCCUGGUGGCCUCGUUCCUGGCGCCCGGAGUCCCUGCUGCGGCCCCACCCCCGGGCGGUCACGGUGACCCAUGCUGCCCAGCCUGGAGGUAAAAUCGUUCGUGGCUGUGGCUUCAGCAUGUCGUCCUCGGUGAAAACCCCAGCACUGGAAGAGCUGGUUCCUGGCUCCGAAGAGAAGCCGAAAGGCAGGUCGCCUCUCAGCUGGGGCUCUCUGUUUGGUCACCGAAGUGAGAAGAUUGUUUUUGCCAAGAGCGACGGCGGCACAGAUGAGAACGUACUGACCGUCACCAUCACGGAGACCACGGUCAUCGAGUCAGACUUGGGUGUGUGGAGCUCGCGGGCGCUGCUCUACCUCACGCUGUGGUUCUUCUUCAGCUUCUGCACGCUCUUCCUCAACAAGUACAUCCUGUCCCUGCUGGGAGGCGAGCCCAGCAUGCUAGGUGCGGUGCAGAUGCUGUCCACCACGGUUAUCGGGUGUGUGAAAACCCUCGUUCCUUGCUGUUUGUAUCAGCACAAGGCCCGGCUUUCCUACCCACCCAACUUCCUUAUGACGAUGCUGUUUGUGGGUCUGAUGAGGUUUGCAACUGUGGUUUUGGGUUUGGUCAGCCUGAAAAAUGUGGCGGUUUCGUUUGCUGAGACGGUGAAGAGCUCCGCCCCCAUCUUCACGGUGAUCAUGUCUCGGAUGAUUCUGGGGGAGUACACAGGGCUGCUGGUCAACCUCUCCCUCAUCCCAGUCAUGGGCGGGCUGGCGCUGUGCACGGCCACUGAGAUCAGCUUCAAUGUCCUGGGGUUCUCGGCCGCACUGUCCACCAACAUCAUGGACUGUUUGCAAAAUGUUUUUUCAAAAAAGCUGCUCAGCGGGGACAAAUACAGGUUCUCGGCCCCGGAGCUGCAGUUCUACACCAGCGCCGCUGCGGUGGCCAUGCUCGUCCCGGCCCGGGUUUUCUUUACGGACGUCCCAGUGAUCGGGAGGAGUGGGAAGAGCUUCAGCUACAACCAGGACGUGGUGCUGCUGCUUCUGACAGACGGAGUCCUGUUCCACCUUCAGAGCGUCACGGCGUACGCCCUCAUGGGGAAAAUCUCCCCGGUGACUUUCAGCGUCGCCAGCACCGUGAAACAUGCCUUGUCCAUCUGGCUCAGCGUAAUCGUUUUCGGCAACAAGAUCACCAGCUUGUCGGCCGUUGGCACAGCCCUGGUGACCGUUGGGGUCCUGCUCUACAACAAAGCCAGGCAACACCAGCAGGAGGCGCUGCAGAGCCUGGCUGCAGCCACUGGCCGGGCCCCAGACGACACAGUGGAGCCGCUGCUUCCACAGGACCCCAGGCAGCAUCCCUGAGAGCAGGAAGCUGCCAGCUGCUGCUGUCCUCGUGACACUGCAUCCCCCAGAAAUGGGCAGGGACGCCCUCCUCCAUGGCCCUGCUGGGGUGCAGGACAUGGGGAGCUAAGUUGGCCAUUGCCUGCGGCUUUCUCGGUUUGUCGGUGAAGACCAGCAGAAACUCAAACUGGGGAUUCCAGGUAUCAGCUUCCUGGAGUAGAGACCAGACCAGUAGCUGACUGUGUCCGCCGAGCCCAUCCCCGUGUAAUGUGAAAACAGCCUCUGAGGCUCCCAUGCUGGGGGUGCCCACUUCCUCUCUGGGCGACACCCCAGGGUCCACCGGGAGCCAGAGGUGGGUCCAGUGCCAACGAGAGCCGCUCCCUGCCACAGCCAAGAGAGCCCUCGGCUUCCCACACCAGCCAUCGAAGGCCCUGAGGCCCUGGACCGGCGGCAGACUGGCCCUGGGCAUGAGGCCACAGAGCAGGGCCGAAGGGAGGGGACAGAGGGCCCUGGAAGGAAGGGUCUCCUGCUGCCACGGUGGGCACUCAGAACUUCUCCCCACCUGACCCAGGGCUGUGGGCAUCCUCAGACUAUCCCAGAGGCAUCGCAAGCCUCAAGCUGCAGCAUUGCACGGCACUCAAGGGCUAUGACCACGGAGGCCGUUCAGUCGCUUCUGUUUAGAGGAAGGCCCCCUACCUCUUCCACACCCUGCCCUCCUAUCCCUUCCACACCCUGGGCUGCGUGAGCUCCCCGCAACCCCAGGGCACCCUGCCCUCCUACCUGUGGGGGUUUCCAGCCCUGAGGUUGAGGACAAACCUCUCGUGUUUAACUUGGGAGGAGAUGUGUACGUUCCUUUUCUUUUUUGGACUCUGAGUAUGAGGCAGGCUGUUCUGAGGUCCCCGUGGGGUGAGCCUGUCUGUCCUCCCUCAGAGCCCACUGUUCCUAUCAUCAUCUAGCACCUGUCCGGUUCCCCACGUGAGCCUUGGGCAGGACGCUGCAGUGUUGAUGGUUUGGGUUACGUGGCGUUUACCUGGGCGCCGUCCUUACUGAAAAAGGAAACGUCCACACUGAAUGUUUCUGGGGCGCGUGGUGUGUGUCAGGCGCCCACCCUGUCCCACUCUCCCCAAGGGACAGUAGUACGGCACACUGGGGCCACCAGCCAGCUCAACUCAUCCUCCUGUGUCACGCACCCCCGAGGGCGCAGGAGGCCUGAGGAGUGGCUACUGGAGCCGUGUGUUAGGCAGAGGCUUCUGACCAUGUCUGAGCUCUUUACCCCCAAUCUCGCAGCUGGCGGAUUCCCAUGCCCGGUGCAGCCUGUUGCCAGCCAGCCUUUGAGACCCAGAGCUCCAGGGCUUGUCAGAGGCAGCAUGGGGCUCCAGUGGUCCCGAGUCUCAUUUCCCUGCCUGCUCUUUAGGCCUUUGGCACCCAUGGUCACUUCACUGGCUUUCCAUUUGGCUUCUCACCUGGGAAAUACAAAAAUAGCCCCUCCUGAAGAUAAAAUCAUUCAGAAACAGAGCAAUAAUUCUGACUCAUUAACUUCUACCUACUCAAAAAAGUCUGCCAUGAUGAUGGACCGAAGUGAGGCUUUUUAACCCACAAGUAACCUUUUUAUUUUUUUGAGACAGUCUUGCUCUGUCUGUCACCCAGGCUGGAGUACAGUGGCAUGAUCUUGGCUCACUGCAGCCUCGACUUCCUGGGCUCAAAUGAUCCUCCCACCUCAGCCUCCCAUGUGGCUGGAACCACAGGCACGUGCCACCAUGCCUGGCUAUUUUUUUGUUGAGCUGGGCUCUCGCUUUGUUGCCCAGGCUGGUCUUGAACUCCUCGGCUCAAGCAAUCCUUCCCACUCAGCCUCCUGUAGUGUCGAGAAUAUAGGCGUGGGCUACUACACCUGCUUCAGCCGCUUCUAUAAAACCGCUGACCUGUGUGUGGAGGACAGGCCAGGUGUGUGCUCACUGCGCUGCGAAGAUGUUUUGUCACGUGACUUUCCCCGGAUUUCCAUUUCUUUUUUUCUGCUUUCCUCAAAAACUAAUAGAAGACUGGGUGCGGUGGCUCACGCCUCUAAUCGCAGCACUUUGGGAGGCAGCAGCUGGCGGAUCACAAGGCCAGGAGUUCGAGACCAGCCUGGCCAACAUGAUGAAACCCUGUCUCUACCAAAAAUACAAAAAUUAGCUGGGUGCGAUGGUGGGUGCCUGUAAUCCCAGAUACUCAGGAGGCUGAGGCAGGAGAAUUGUUUGAACCCCGGAGAUGGAGGUUGCAGUGAGCCAAGAUCGUGCCAUUGCACUCCAGCCUGGGCAACAGGGCAAGAUUCCGUCUCAAAAACAAACACUAUUAGAAAAUGCCCUGGAGGUGGCGGGGAGUUGUUGAUUUGUGAGGACAGAUUGAAAGCAACUCCCAGGGUGGCCUUGUCCACCUCCCCGUCGAGAAUGUGGCUGCCGGCCUCUUUGAAGAUUGUGGUCUGGCAUAAGGAGAGGUGCAGGCGCCUGGUUCUGAGCACCUUGGAAUUUCCAGCCGCACAGCAUCUGGUGCCCUCCCCUCCACCCUCACAAGGAGCUGCCAUCCUGUUUGGAUUUUCUGUUUGUGGACCAGAAACAAACGUUUUUCCAAAGGAUUAGCAAAUAGGGUAAUUUCCUGUGUAACGCUGCUCUGGGGCCUCUUCCUCAUCCUGGCAGAAGGAGCCUGGAGCCCAUGAGGCAGCCAGCACUGUGCCCUUGCUCAGUCGUGCUGUCCCCUCCCUCUCCCUCAGUCUCCUCUCCAUGCCCAAGUCAGUUUCCAGCCGCUGGUCUUCAUGGCAUUCCCAGCACAGCCGGGCACCAAGAGGCAAAACCCAAGGCCUGGCUUGGCCGUGUUAACGAUUGUACAGACAUUUUUUAAAAUAACUUUGUGUAAUACUUUUCUGGAAUAGUAAGUUCUUGUUGAACUGUCACAGGUGAGCUUCUAGGAACACACCAGGUGUGGUUACUUCCACUGGGUGUGUCCAUGGUCGUGGUCUGUGCUUUUGUAAACGAACAGAACACUUGAACCACCUCCCGAAUUGGGUCAUCGGCUUCUUUACGUUGAUACUUAAGAGAUUUGCAGCUCUCUUUCAAGGAAACUUCCCCUACUGAAAGGCAUAAAAAGGUUAAAAAAGAAAAUCCGAGAGUCCCAAUUCCCUGUAUAACAGCAUUAAAAUAAUCUGCCUGCCUGGAAAGAUGAGAACACUGUUGCACAACCCAAAAUGUGUCUUUAAUUUGUGAAAAAUUACCAUGGUGAGUCAGACAGUCAUUUUAAACAGCUGAACAGAGACUAUCAUCAGCAAAUAGAGCUCAGCUUUGUAGCUGCCUUUAAAAUCCUUGUCCCAAAUCCGGUGAGCUCUGCUUGCUGCCGCCGCGCUCCUGGGUGAUCACUCAGACGGGUCAGUGGGAAUAACAGGCCAACAAGACAGCUUUUUACAUGUGUCCAAAGGAUGGCCUUUCGAAGGCCUGGAAGUAUUUCACUGUUGGAAGAAGUAAACAAGAAUGACAUUCCAGAUGGAAAUAGAAUUCUCUCUCUUGCCUUUGACCAACAUGGUACUAAGGGGUUUCUUCUUUCCCAAUGUAUGUACGUGCCCUGCUGGGGGCCUUACUUUAUAGAAUGAGAGCAUCCGAGCUUCCCUAAUGAAUCUGGCUAGUUCUGUGUCUGGCUGAGGAUACAGGAGUGGGACAUCCACUCUCGGAUCCCUCAGAGCACAGAAACCUUCAGCUUUGCUGUCUCUGAAGUAUUUCCUCCAGUUUCCCUGCGGGCCCCUAUGUUUGAGUUUGAUGGCUGCUGGAUCCUCACUCAACGAAAACUCGGUUGGAAACUGUUCCGCCUGGCAGUCCUUUUUUGUUGUUUUCCAUCUCAUUUCCCUUCCAUCUGAAAGUGGCAUUCAGCUGACUUGCUCAUUUAGACUGUUCACGGAGUCUGAAUCUGCCAACGUGGUGUUGGAGGCUCCACCUUGAAAAGGGCCACAGUCAGGGCAACUUUCCCCAUACAGGAAAACUUGAAAAUUACAUCAACAGUCUACGUCACAGCCAAAUUAUAUUUCCUUUAUACCAAACAAAACUAUGGAGAACUAAAAGUACAUCACACAAAACGUUUAUAGUGUUUUGCAUGUGACCUAUUUCAGUAUUUAUAUAACUAGAUUAGUGCUUUCUAGCAAACGGUUCUGUUAAUUAGCGAGUCACUGUUGAUUCUGCUGUGGUGGUAAGUUGAUACCGUGUAACUAAUCCCGUGGAUGCCUCCUCGUUAUUUUUGUCCAAACGAAGCAGCCGUGGUAGUAGCUGUCUAUGAUUCUUGCUCAGCAAAGUAAAAUAAAUGUUAAAUAUGGA